AUGGUCAGUCUUACAGCAGUUGGGAAUCUUUCUCCCCAGGUGAAAUUGACACUAGUGGGACCUCCAAUGGCAGGUGAGUCACUGCUGUGGGCAUUUCCUCUGCCAUUCUCCUGCUCUCCGGGCACUCUGAUGGAGCAUGUGGCACCUCGUCUCCAGGCCUAGGAUAUAUCACUGCUUUUAUCUGAUGGUGUUGACCGUCCACUGGACCCACCAGAGAAUGGCAGUAGAACCUCUUUAUUCCAAGAGCACCCCUAAAGUAAGAUCAACACACGUAGGGCAGAUGUCAGCUUAUGGGGACAACUCCUCUGUGCCCGACUAGCAUCAUUAGCAUCGUCCUCUCACAAGGAUGUAGCACUGUGAAGUUCUGUUCUAGGUGGCAAGAACCAUGCACUUCUCCAGCUCAGCCAGGGCAGCAGAUGAGAACUUUGACUAUUUGUUCAAGAUUAUCCUCAUUGGGGAUUCCAAUGUGGGGAAGACGUGUGUGGUGCAGCAUUUCAAGUCUGGAGUCUACACUGAGACACAGCAGAACACGAUUGGAGUGGACUUUACCGUGCGUUCCCUUGAUAUUGACGGCAAAAAAGUGAAGAUGCAGGUGUGGGACACAGCUGGCCAGGAGCGCUUCCGCACCAUCACCCAAAGCUACUACCGCAGUGCCCACGCAGCCAUCAUCGCCUAUGACCUCACCCGGCGGUCCACGUUCGAGUCCAUCCCUCACUGGAUUCAUGAGAUAGAGAAAUAUGGAGCUGCAAAUGUGGUCAUUAUGCUGAUUGGAAAUAAAUGUGACCUCUGGGAAAAGCGGCACGUCCUGUUCGAGGAUGCCUGCACACUGGCUGAGAAGUACGGCCUCCUGGCCGUUUUGGAGACAUCUGCCAAGGAGUCAAAGAACAUAGAAGAAGUCUUCGUGCUCAUGGCCAAGGAGCUGAUCGCGCGCAACAGCCUGCACCUAUAUGGGGAGAGUGCCCUGAACGGCCUCCCCCUGGACUCCAGCCCCGUUCUUAUGGCCCAGGGUCCAAGUGAAAAGACCCACUGCACUUGCUAAGAUGUUUGCAAAGCCAGUUGCACCCACCAAAGAGGCCGCCUCUGAAACCAAAGGUAGCCAGGAUACCGUAGUGUUGCCCCAGUGGCGCUUUAGACCCCAGCGUGGACUUGCCGCUCACCCCUAAUCCUCCCAGUCUGGAUGGGCCACACUUCUCCCUUGACUCACACCACAGGUCAUAGCUGCUGACUCUCAGGAAAACCAGCACCAUUGUUUUCACUGACUCUUGACUCCUGGAGAAGGCAGGACUUCAGGCUAGGAGAGGGAGGACGAAGUGUACUCUUCUCCCCUUUCACUUUUCUGUCUCCCUAGAGCUUCUGCUGCUUUCUACUGAAUUUUGUUUCUUGCUUGAAGAAGAGGGUAGUGAAGGAAAGGAGGAAGGCAAAACAGCAAGAGAGAGAAGAGGCUGUUUGGAACAUUCUGGAACAGUUUGAAACAGCUCAGGCAGGGAGAAUGGAACGAAAGCCUGCAAUGAGAAACCAGAAUGCUGCUAUCAUUUUGUUCCUGACAUUCACACCUCAGGUCUUCACUUUGGGGAGCGAAGCCUUUUAGCAGAAAUACCAGAAGUACCAUCUUGCCAAAUGGUCAGGAACUGUCUGAUAGAGAUGGAACUGGAAUUCACUCUAUUCUAGCAGGGCUGACUUGGCCACCCUCUUGGGAUAGGGGAAGACACCUGCAAUUUUUUUUCUUUCUUUUUUUUUUUUUUUUUUUUGAGACAGGGUCAUACUCUGUCACCCAAGCUGGAGUAUAGUGGUGGGAUCUUGGCUCACUGCAACCUCUACCUCCUGGGUUCAAGAGGUUCUCCCACCUCAGUCUCCCAAGUGGCUGGGACUACAGACACACGCCACCACUCCUGGCUAAUUUUUGUAUUUUUUGUAGAGACAAGGUUUCACCAUGUUGCUCAGGCUGAUCUUGAACUCCUGAGCUCAGGUGAUCUGCCCACCUUGGCUUCCCAAAGUGCUGGGAUUACAGGCAUGAGCCACCAUGCCUGUUCUUUUUUUUUUUUUUUUUUUUUGAGACUGAGUCUCACUCUGUCACUCAGGCUGGAAUGCAGUGGCAUGAUCUCGGCUCACUGCAACCUCAACCUCCACCUCCUGGGUUCAAGCAAUUCUCCUGCCUCAGCCUCCCAAGUAGCUGGGACUACUGGCACUCACUACCACGCCCAGCUCAUUUUUUUUGUAUAUUUAGUAGAGACUGGGUUUCACUACGUUGGUCAGGCUGGUCUUGAACUCCUGACCUCAUGAUCCACCCGUCUCGGCCUCCUAAAGUGCUGGGAUUACAGGCAUGAGCCACCAUGCCCGGCCCUUUUUUUUUUUUUUUUGAGACAGAGUUUCGCUCUUGUUGCCCAGGCUGGAGUGCAAUGGUGUGACCUCGGCUCACUGCAACUUCUGCCUUCCAGAUUCAAGUGAUUCUCCUGCCUCAACCUCCCUAGUAGCUGGGAUUACAGCCUCCCGCCACCACGCCUAGCUAAUUUUUGUGUUUUUAGUAGAGGCAGGGUUUCACCACGUUGGCCAGGCUGGUCUCGAACUCCUGACCUCAUGAUCCACCUGUCUCGUGGCCUCCCAAAGUGCUGGGAUUACAGGUGUGAACCACCGCACCUGGCCUUUUUUUAUUAUUAUUAUUGUAGAAAUGAAGUCUUGCUACGUUGCCCAGGCUGGUCUCCAAUUCCUGAGCUCACAGGUUUCUCCCACCUCAGCCUCCCAAAGUGCUGGGAUUACAGGCAUGAGCCACCAUGCCUGGCACAAUUUCUUUCUAGAACCCAAAUCAUCUGCCAGAUCAGAAGUCAUUUUUAAAUUAAAAUUAAAUUGGUUCAUAGAUGAAUAUCAA